CCUGGCCGCCUCUCGCCCGGCGGGCCUCAGGUGACGCGGCCGCGGCUUAACUUUCGCACCUGAGGCUCUCGGAGCGGCCUCGGGGCGCGCCCACCUGGAGGUUGGAAUUACACAGGGUCGAAAAAGCUGAGUCCUGGAGGCGAGGCGCUAUGAAAAGAAGCAAAGAAUUGAUAACUAAAAAUCAUAGUCAAGAGGAAACAAGUAUUCUUCGUUGUUGGAAAUGUAGAAAAUGUAUAGCAAGCUCUGGUUGUUUUAUGGAGUAUCUUGAGAAUCAAGUGAUUAAGGAUAAAGAUGAUUCAGUUGAUGCUCAAAAUAUUUGUCAUGUGUGGCACAUGAAUGUAGAAGCCCUUCCAGAAUGGAUAAGCUGCCUAAUCCAAAAAGCCCAGUGGACAGUUGGAAAACUGAAUUGUCCUUUCUGUGGGGCCCGUUUAGGGGGCUUUAAUUUUGUCAGCACUCCAAAAUGUUCCUGUGGCCAGCUUGCAGCUGUACAUCUCUCCAAGAGCCGGACUGAUUAUCAGCCAACACAGGCAGGCAGACUAAUGAGACCAUCAGUGAAAUACUUGUCACAUCCUAGAGUUCAGUCAGGUUGUGACAAGGAAGCUCUGCUGACAGGUGGUGGCUCUGAAAACAGAAAUCACAGGCUUUUAAACAUGGCCCGAAAUAAUAAUGACCCUGGAAGAUUAACAGAAGCACUCUGCCUGGAGGUGCGACCAACAUAUUUUGAGAUGAAGAACGAAAAACUGCUGUCCAAAGCAUCAGAACCAAAAUACCAGCUUUUUGUUCCCCAGCUUGUGACUGGCAGAUGCGCUACAAGAGCUUUUCAUAGAAAAUCACAUAGUUUGGAUCUGAACAUCAGUGAGAAACUGACUUUAUUACCCACUUUAUAUGAAAUACAUAGUAAGACUACUGCCUAUUCCAGACUAAAUGAAACACAGCCUAUUGACCUUUCAGGCUUGCCUUUACAAUCUAGUAAAAAUAGCUAUUCCUUUCAGAAUCCAUCCAGUUUUGAUCCUAGUAUGCUGCUGCAAAGAUUUUCAGUGGCCCCCCAUGAGACCCAGACACAAAGAGGAGGAGAAUUUCAGUGUGGUCUAGAAGCUGCUUCAGUGUAUUCUGACCAUACUAAUACUAACAAUCUGACUUUCCUGAUGGACCUGCCCUCAGCUGGCAGGAGCAUGCCGGAGGCCUCAGACCAGGAAGAGCACCUCUCCCCUCUGGACUUCCUGCACUCAGCCAAUUUUUCAUUGGGCAGCAUUAAUCAGAGGCUUAAUAAGAGAGAAAGGAGCAAGUUGAAGAAUCUAAGAAGGAAACAACGAAGGCGUGAAAGAUGGCUACAGAAGCAGGGUAAAUACUCAGGAGUGGGAUUGCUGGAUCAUAUGACUUUGAAUAAUGAGAUGAGUACAGAUGAAGACAAUGAAUAUGCAGAAGAAAAGGAUAGCUACAUCUGUGCAGUGUGUCUGGACGUUUAUUUCAACCCUUAUAUGUGUUACCCUUGCCAUCACAUCUUCUGUGAGCCCUGCUUACGGACUCUGGCCAAAGACAAUCCUUCAAGCACUCCAUGCCCAUUGUGUCGGACAAUUAUUUCUAGAGUCUUUUUCCAAACAGAAUUGAACAAUGCCACAAAAACUUUCUUUACUAAAGAAUAUUUGAAAAUAAAACAAAGCUUUCAGAAAUCCAACUCUGCAAAAUGGCCCCUACCAAGCUGCAGAAAAGCAUUUCAUCUUUUUGGAGAUGUACAAAUGAAGAAAAUGAAGACUAUACAAUAAGAGCAAAUCCGAAGACUCAUGACUAAAUUGACUUUGCCAUGCUAUCACUGUUUAGUACAUAGAUAAUGAAAAUACGUCUCAAAAGUAUCAGAUUUGACAAAGUCAUAUUUAUGGCAGCGGCAGCCCAUCUGGAACAGCUGCUACUAUGAAGCCAGCUGCAGUCGGGGAGGCACAAGCCAGGGCUGCACAUUCCACAGAGCUGGCAGGAGCCAGGAACAGGUGGGAGCCCUGCCCCUUUCCAAGUUAGCAGGGUGGGAGCCCUGCCUACCCAGGCAAAGUUGCAGCCACCCAGCCAUGGCUUCGGACCGAGACAUCCUUGUACUCUUGGGGACUGGGGAAGCCCCCUUGCCCCUGCAGGCUCAGAAAUGCCUACUCCUGCUGCCUGGCCUCUCCAUGCUCCUGGCACCCACUCCAAUUUCACAGCAAAGUUGAAGCCAAGCCCAGGCACUGUCGCAACCCAGCCAAGUGUGUACACUCUCAGGGCAGUCCUGACAUGCCAGCCCCCUGCUGCCUAGGCCCACUCCAAACUCUGGGUGCUGACAAGCAUGGGAGGAAGGCUGAGGGGAGCUGAGGGCAGCUCAGCGCAACCUGCAUACACCGCUUGGCAAGAAUAGCUUGGGCACUGUGGGCACCGUGGAUGGCAGGUUGAUGGUGGCAGGAGGCAGACAGGCUCCUGGGCAGAAAGGGGACAGGUCCCUGGUAAAGCCCCACCUUCUUCAAACCUGAAGACUGGGGGCUGGGCUGUCAGUUCUGUGGACCAGAGUGAGAACUUACAGUGCUUUUUCCAGGCCUGCCUAUGGCCACCCAUGAACCAGUCAGCAUGCACUUCCUCCCCUCUUUAGCCCAUAAAAACCCUGGACUCAGCCAGACUCAGGCAGACAGUGGGACAACCUACCUGACAAUAUGACCUGUGAGUCUCCUCUCCACUGAGGGCUGUAGAGACAGCGGGACAACCUGCCUGUGAAUAGGAGAUACCCACUGUGGGUCUCCUGAGAACUGUUCUACCACUCAGUGAAGCUCCUCUCCACCUUGCUUACCCUCCAGUUGUCUGCAUACCUCAUUCCUCCUGAAUGUGGGACAAGAACUCAGGACCUGCUGAGUGGCAGGACUAAAAGAACUGUAACACAAUAAGGGCUGAAACACACCCCCGCCCCAUGCUCGCCACAUUGACGGUGACAAGACAAGAAGAGCUGCAGCCCUUUGAGGAGCCCAGAUGUAGAGAUCCCUGAGCCAGGGCUGUGACACCCUCCUUGGGGUUCUGCAGUUCCUGGAGUCUCCAAGCUUCCAGGCACCACUGCAUUUACCUCGUCCUGACUCGGGUGCCCACAGCAGAAGCCGCAUGAAGUAUAUCUCAUCCAGCCACAGCCACACACAGAGCCAACACCUGGAGCUCCCUGCCCCGCCACAGCAGCCAGCAUGCCUGGCUGUGCACAGUGGCUGGACCUCACGCUUGCUCAACCACACACCCCUUGCCAUUCUGCACCUGGCUUGCACUUGGCAGAUGUGGGAUCUGAGCCAGUAGUAAGAGCCAAGCACAGCCUGCCAGGCCAAGUGGGUUGAACUGGCCCAGCAGGCACAAGCAGUACUCAGGCAGAAGAUGCCGUCAGCUACAGAGGUUUCUGGCUGGUGAAGUGACACCCUAGGGAUCCUGUGACAAUAGUUAACAAAGGCACCAGUACUCUGUAUAAAGAUUCCUAAUAAUGCGUUCAUUAGCAGAAGCUCUAUUUAUUUAGUUUUAAUAUUUUAUAGUUGUCCCACAAGUUUAAAACAAAUAGAAAGUAACAGAGCCUUGGUGUCAGGGUGUCUUAGAGAUGUGCAGUGGUCAAGGAAUACCAAUUUCUGGCUUUAGGUCUAAGUUAUCAACAUGACUUCAGCGAUAUCAUAGGAUCUCUGUUUUGAUCUGUAAAAUAGGAAUAAUUAUGUCUUCCUCACCUAACUAAUAUAGUAGUAAAGAUUAAAUGGGCUAAUGUGAAAGUACAUUGUAAAUUAUAACUAAUUGGAAUAUAAAAAUAUAAGGAAUGAAGGUAAUGCAAUAUCUAAUACCUUUUUCUGCUUUGGGAAUUUGUUACUAUAUGAACAUACAAUAUGGACAUAAAAUAUAAUUUCAUCUUUUAUGAAACCGUAGUUUAUCAAAGCAUGAACUACUGUGCAGUUUUCGUUAUUUAACAAUUAUGACAUUAUGGGACCUGGUAGAAAAGUCCAGAUAUGAGGAACUGUGAUCUUCAGGGAACAGGAGGAACUUCUGCAUAAGACCAACAAAAUCAGUACAGCUACUACCUACACCAAAAGGAGGUUGGUCUUCUGCGUAAGACCAACAAGAUCAGUACAGUACUACCUACACCAAAAGGAGAUAGAAGCAGAGCCCCUAUGAUUGUGGCAAAAGAAAAAUUGGUGCAUGAAAUUGGUACUCUCAAAGAAAGUAACAUAAGAAUAUAACUUUACACAGUGAUUUGAAUGAAGAAAAUAGUUUAAGGACAUUAUAUAAGCACAUACUACUUUAUAAAGUGGUCAGUAACUGUAAAAAUUUAAUAUCUAGAGAUUUGGUAUAGAUAGGUUUUAUUUUUAUUUUUUACUCAUUUAUUUUAUUUUUUUGAGACAAAGUCUGGCUCUAUCGCCCAGGCUAGAGUGUAGUGGCGCAAUCUCAGCUCACUACAACCUCUGCCUCCUGGGUUCAAGCAGUUCUUCUGCCUCAGCCUCCCAAGUAGCUGGGAUUACAGGUGCGUGCUACCAUGCCAAGCUUUUUAGUAGAGAAGGAGUUUCGUCAUGUUGGCCAGGCUGGUCUUGAAUAAUGAAUGACCUCAGGUGAUCCACCCGCCUUGGCCUCCCAAAAGUGCUGGGAUUAUAGGCAUGAGCCACUGUUCCUGGCCAUAGAUAGGUUUUAAUAGGUCACAUUUAGCCCCCAAAAUAUGAAAUCAAAUGUAAGAAAUCGAGUCUUAAAGGAUUUCAUACCAAAGAAAAGUAAGUUUAUUAUUUUAAGAGUGUUCUUCAAAACAGUCCCUUGUAUUCUACCUUCUAUGCUAUACCCAAAGUUCUAAAAGAAUGGAGUACCUUCUGGAUAACUCUACACUUUCCCUUGUCUUUUUGUAUUCUGAGGUAGUACAGAAGCUAUAAUUUAAAGCAGUUGCUUCCUUGUGAUUUCUUCUUGUCUUCCCCAUAGGAGUUCCAAAUAACUUAAUUUUUUAAGUGUGUGUUUAUGAAGGAGGUUCAAAGUAGCAUUAUUACACCACCCAACAUAAGAAAUAUAUAUAUUCUAUCAGGAGCUCAGCUGAGCUGGGAAAGAGCUGAGUUAUCAGGUGUCUGGAGUAGCCGAUUAAAGUAUCAAGCCAAAAAUGAAGGAGUUAAGCCUUUAAUCAUUUACUGCAAUAGUAUAACCAAGAGUCUAAAACCAGAGGAAAUGCUGUCUCCUCCUGUUCAAUUAUCUCAUGCAACAGUGCACACUGGUCCAGGGCCACAUAGAGCAGGGCAGAAGUAAGGAUUCACUCACUGUUGAGAAUGUCCCAAACAAAAGGCUCCAGCAGUUUUUCAGACCCUGAGGUCAGGAGGAUUGGCAAAGAGGAAAGGCUAGGAGUAGGAAAGCAAUGGGCACUGAGUCAGAGUGGAGAAAAGUGUUUCCCCCUCCAACCUCCAUAAGAAAGCCUUUGUAGAGACACAGAAGGACCUCUGCCCAAGCCGUCAGAUAGAUAUAAGUAGUAACAAAGGUGCUGGGAAUAUGAAUAUAAAUACGUAAAAGUGUAUAUGCAGCCAGGGGAGCCUGAGAACUUGACUGCAGCUCCCUUCAGAGAUUGUAAUGCACUGGUUGUACAACAAAUCUGGCUUUUUCCCAUGAAUCCUGCCAGAUAAAGCCUUUGUAAUGGUCUGUUGAGGCCUGAAAAAAAAUCGCACAUAGGAUUUUAAUCAGGAACUGUACUCCUCAAUUACCAAUAUUAUUGAAGCACCUUCUGUAGUUCUUCUUUGUUUACCCUGAUUCCCCUGAAUUUUGUAUUUAUCAUUUCUUUGUAUAAGUAUACAUAUGUAUACUUAAUCAUGUUACUUAAUUUUGCUUGUCUUUUAACUUUUAUAAUGGUAGCAAUGUAUAUAUUCUGCUUUGCUUUGUCAUUCAAUAUUUUUCUCAAAUCCAUUUCAGUAAGUGUGGCCACAUUCUUUUUACUACUACACUGUAGUCAAUUAUGUGAAAAUGCCCCAACCCAACUUAUCCAUUCUCUUGUUGAUGAACAAUUGAGUGGUCCAAUUUUUAUUAUAAACAGUGUUUCUAUAAACACUCUUGUGAUGUCUCCUGGAACAUAAGAGUUACUCUAGAAUAAAUGCCAGGUAGAAACUGGCUGGGUCAUAGGAAAAGCACAUCUUUAACUUCAUAACCUACCCAAAACCGUUUUCCUAAAUGGCUGUGAUGAUUUAUCACCAGCUUUGUCUACCACAUUUGGUAUUUUCAGUCUUUUAGAUUUUACUGAUUUGAUAGGUAGAAAAUGAUAUCUCAUUGGGGUUUUAAUUUCCAUUACUGUGAUUACUGAUGGGGGUUGAACAUAUCUUUAUAUGUGUAUUGAUCAUUAAAUUUCUUCAUCUGUGAAAUGCUUUUUUACGAUUUUCUGUUGGUUGUAUUUUUUUGUUGUUUAAGAAUGUUAAAAUAUUUUCUAGUGACUUUUUUUCUGUUGGUUAUAUGAAUGGCAGUUAUUGUCUCCCAGUCUGUGGGUUCUUUUUACUUUGAUAUAUUUUAAUGAAUUGUAGUUCUUCAAUUUCUUCAUCUUUCUGGUGUGUACUUGCUUAAGAAAUUCUUCUCUUUCCCCAAGGUCAUAAAGAUAUUUUCUUAUGUAUUUUUCAAAUAAUUUGAAAGAUCUUUGAAACUGAUUUGUGUUAAUUUUUUUUUUAUUGAUUUACUUUCUUUGUUGUAGGUAGAGACCCAGUUUCUUUGGAUUUUUUUCCUACCACCAUUUGUUGAAAAUAAUGUAUCAUUUCCUCACUGAUCUACAGUACUAAUCUGUCAUAUUUUAAUUUCCACACUUGGGUCUGUUUUGAGGUCUUUGAGUCCAUUGGUAUAAUUUUUUAUUCCUAUAGCAAUACCAUACUGUUUCAGUCACUAAAAACUUAGUAAGUUUUGAUAUCCCCCCUUCCAAUUUGUUUUGCUGCAAGAGUGUCUUGGCCAUUUUUUGGCCCUUUGCUCUUCCAUAUAAAUUUUUAAAUCACCUGGUCAAGCUGCAUGAAAAACUAUGUUCUACUUGGGAAAUGGGGUCCUAUUAAAUGUAUAAAUCAAUUUGGGGAGUAUUGAUACCUUAGAGUAAAAGUACUUCUAUCAGUGUUGUUUAUCUCUUCAUUUGUUUAGAUCUCCUUUGAUGUCCUAUAAUAAAGUUUUAUAAUGUUUUUAUAAAUAUCUCGCACAUCUUUUGGCUAGAUUUAUUCCCAUGUACUUGCUAUGUUGUCCUCUUCUCUCCUUUUUUGAAACUUCAGUGCAGAAAAAUUGUCCUAGUCACACUUAAUUUAUGGCAUACCAUCAUCACUGUUCCACAUACUCAUUUGUUUUCUUUUUAUCCCCAUAUCCUUCUUUCUACUUCACUCUCAUCCCAUAGCCAACCAUUAUAUUGGGUUUACUUAAUGUGUGUCAUUUUGUGUUCUUAUAGAAUGUAUAUUGUUUCUGCACAUAUAUUUUUAAUUUGUGAAAAUGGUCUUAUAUAUUGCAUUGUUUCUCUUUCACCUAGCACUGCCCUUUAGAUCCAUCCAAGUGGUUAUGCGUACCUCUAAUCUGUGACUUCUAAUUAAUGCUCUACUAAGGUGUGCAUUUACCAUAUUUUGUCUAUCUAUUCACUUUCUAGAAUACUUCCAACUCUCUGCCACAAUAAAAACACUCUAAUGAAUAUCCUACUGUGGGCUGUGAAUAUCUAUUUGGUAUAUAGGCUCCAAAGCAGAAUGUCUGGGUCAUAGGAUAUGAGUAUGCUUGACUAAAUAUUGCCAACAGUUCUCCCAAAUGACUAGCCUAGACACCUAUUAUCAGUGUGUAAGGUUGGGAAAAAUUAGCACUAUGGAAAAUGUUGACAGGGAAUGAGAAUUAGAAACCCUCAUUUUAAUUUACAUUCAUCUGAUAAUAGUUUAAGGUCAUUUUAAAUAUUAGCCUUUCAGAUGCCUCUUUUGUAGUUACUUUGCUUAUUUUACUAUGGGGGUUUCUGCCCUUAUUGGUUUUAUAAAAUUUCUUUUAUAUUCUAGAUAUUAAUUUUUUAUUUACUUUAGACAUUACAAAUUUCUUCUGCCAUUUUUAUCAUCUACAUAUUGUUUGUCCAUGGUAUCUUUCAUUGUAAGGAAUUCUUAACUUUGAUAUAAUUAAAUGUUUUUCGCUUUGUGUCUUAAAUUUUUAUUUAGGUUCUUCCCUAUUCCCAGACCACAGAGGUUUUCACUUUGAUUUUCUUUUUUUGUUGUUGUUUUUUUUUUGUUUUUGUUUUUGUUUUUGUUUUUUUUGAGACAACGUCUCACUCUGUUACCCAGGCUGGAGUGCAGUGGUAUGAUCGGCAGCCUCAACCUUCCAAUUCAGGCAAUUCUCCCACCUCAGACUCCUGAGUAGCUGGGACUACAGGAGCACACCACCAUGCCUGGCUGAUUUUGUUUUUGUAGACACAGGCUCUCACUAUGUUGCCUAGGCUGGUCUUGAACUCCUAGCUCAAGCAAUCCUCCUUCCUCGGCCUCCCAAAGUGCUAGGAUUACAGGCAUGAGCCACCCUGCCAAGCCUCGCUUAGAUGUUUUAAAUAUUUAUUUUGUAGUUUUACUUUUUCGGUCUUUAUCUAGAAUCUUCCCCUUAUAUUUUGUUAAAGGUUCAACAUCUGUCUUUUUUCAUAUAAUAGCCUACUUUUCUGAAUAUUAUACAAUCUUGCUGAGAUUUUUAUAUGGUUUCCUAUUGUUGUCUAGAAAUAUAUUUUUUUGCAAUCUUUUUUAUUUUUUAUUAUACUUUAAGUUUUAGGGUACAUGUGCACAAUGUGCAGGUUAGUUACAUAAGUAUACAUGUGCCGUGCUGGUGUGCUGCACCCAUUAACUCAUCAUUUAGCAUUAGAUAUAUCUCUUAAUGCUAUCCCUCCACCCUCCCCCCACCCCACAACAGUCCCCAGAGUGUGAUGUUCCCCUUUCUGUGUCCAUGUGUUCUCAUUGUUCAAUUCCCACCUAUGAGUGAGAACAUGCGGUGUUUGGUUUUUUGUCCUUGCGAUAGUUUACUGAGAAUGAUGAUUUCCAGUUUCAUCCAUGUCCCUACAAAGGACAUGAACUCAUCUCUUUUAUGGCUGCAUAGUAUUCCAUGGUGUAUAUGUGCCACAUUUUCUUAAUCCAAUCUAUCAUUGUUGGACAUUUGGGUUGGUUCCAAGUCUUUGCUAUUGUGAAUAGUGCUGCAAUAAACAUACGUAUGCAUGUGUCUUUAUAGCAGCAUGAUUUAUAGUCCUUUGGGUAUAUACCCAGUAAUGGGAUGGCUGGGUCAAAUGGUAUUUCUAGUUCUAGAUCCCUGAGGAAUCGCCACACUGACUUCCACAAUGGUUGAAAUAUAUUGAUAUUGGUAUGUUGUUAUCAUAUUUAACAACCUUACGAAAUUGUCUUAUUAAGUCUAAUUAUUUAUAAGGUUUUUGUGGCUUUCAGUGAAGACAAUAUUAAAUAAGGACAAUUUUAUAUCUUUCAAUUUAAUGCAUAUGCUUUUUUCUCUUUGCACUUACCAGACUUUCUGAGCUAGGACUUCUAUUUGAUUUUGAACGGAAAAAGUAAUCAUAGCAUCCUGAUUUUAAAAGGAAUGCUUUUGGCUGGGCGCAGUGGCUCAUGCCUGUAAUCCCAACACUUUGGGAGGCCGAGGCAGGCGGAUCACGAGGUCAGGAGAUCGAGACCAUCCUGGCUAACACGGUGAAACCCCGUCUCUACUAAAAAUACAAAAAAAUUAGCCUGGCGUGGUGGCGGGUGCCUGUAGUCCCAGCUACUCAGGAGUCUGAGGCAGGAGAAUGGCGUGAAUCCGGGAGGCAGAGCUUGCAGUGAGUGGAGAUCGCGCCACUGCACUCCAGCCUGAGCAACAAGGCGAGACUCCAUCUCAAAAAAAAAAAAAAAAGUAAUGCUUUUAAUAUUUACAAAUAGGUAUAAUUGUUGCUCUGUAUUCUUGGUAAGUACCCUUCAUCAGGUUUUAAGAAUGUUCUCUCAUCUGUUCCUAAUUUCUAAUGCCUGUAGUUUUUCUUAAAUGGAGUUUAAUUUUGUGGAUGUUUUUUCAGCAUUUCUUGAAAUUAUCAUACGGCUUUACUUCCUCAAUUUGUUAAUGCACUGAAUCAUAUUAAUAGAUUGUAAUUGAUGUUCUAAUGUUAGGACAUUAGAACACUGCUAGAUUUGGUUUGCUAAUAUUUUGUCUCAGAAUUUUACUUAUUUAUGAGUAAAAUUGUAUUUAUUUUUUAUACUGUGUUUUGUCAAUUUCUUCCUAAGUUUAUAUAUCUUUUUGCUGAGAAUUUUUUUUGUGUCAAAUUUGUUAGCCUUUGUUUAUAAUAUUUUAAUCUGUCUUGUAUAUCUAGUUAUGCUCUUUGAAUUCUGAUUAUCUACUCAUUUUUCUGUGAUGUUGCUGAGUAUUUGUCAAUUUUAUUAUUCCAUUUAAAUUACCAAAUUUGAGAAUUGUCUAUUGUAUCUUUGUUUUUAUACAUUCAUUUCUGUUCUUUAUUAAAUCCUUUCUGUUACUGUC